AUGAGUGAGAACAAAAAUCUGGACAAGCAGGAAUGGAAUCCUACAAUGAACAAAAACCAAUUGCGAAAUGGUUUGAGGCAGAGUGUGGUUCAGUCAGGGAUGUUGGAAGCUGGAGUAGACAGGAUUAUUUCUCAGAUGGUGGAUCCAAAACUUAACCACAUCUUCAGGCCACAAAUAGAACGAGCAAUUCAUGAGUUCCUGGCGGCCCAGAAAAAAGCAGCUGUGCCAGCACCCCCUCCAGAGCCCGAAGGCCAGGACCCUCCAGCUCCAUCCCAGGACACUUCCUAAGAAUAUGCCAGACACCUUUUGAAAGCUAAUUUUUGGUGAAGAAAUGGAUUCGGUUACGUAAGAGUGCAACUUCAGACUGAAGGUAGGCCAAGGUCGUCACUGAUCUCAAGAUUUCAACCUUGACCAUGGGCAG